AGUACCUUUUAUCACUUCUGUAUCAUUUAUUUAUUUCGGGAAGGGAGUGUAGUGGCUGCCAGGAGAGGGAGGCACACAUAUAAAUUGUGGACAAAGCCUAGAAACCUAGGCAUUGCCCCUGCUCAUAGGAAGUCAUAUGCAUGGAACAUACGCACUGGAGUGCUAGUUAGACAGCUGGGAUGAUAGAGCAGGGGAUCCAGGCUGAUACAUCAGGGGAACUUGCAGAGAGAAUAGGGGAUCCAGGAUGAUAGAGCAGGAUAAGGACAGCUGUGGAUGGAGCAGGACGACUGGAUAAUGGAGCAUGGAGCCAGGAUGAUGGAACAAGCAGCCAGGAUGAUGGACAGGGAGCUGGGAUGAUGGAGCCGGGAGCUGGGAUGAUGGAGCAGAGCAGCUGGGAUGAUGGAGCAGGGCAGCUGGGAUGAAACAGCAGGGAGCUGGAAUGAUAGAGCACGGCAGUUGGGAUGAUGGAGGAGGGAAGCUGGGAUGAUGGAGCAGGGAAGCCGGGAUGAUGGAGCAGGGAAGCCGGGAUGAUGGAGCAGGGAGCCAGGAUGAUGGAGCAGGGAGCCUAGAUGAUGGAGCUGGCAGCUGGGAUGACAGAGUGGGGAGCAGGAUGAUGGAGCAGGGAGCCAGGAUGAUGGAGCGGGGGGGCCAGGAUGAUGGAGCGGGGAGCUGGGAUGAUGGAGCAGGCAGCCAGGAUGAUGGAGUGGGGAGCCCAGAUGUUGGAGCAGGCAGCCAGGAUGAUGGAGUGGGGAGCGAGGAUGAUGGAGCAGGGGAGCCGGGAUGAGGGAGCAGGCAGCUGGGAUGACGGAGCAGGGAGUGGGAUGAUGGAGCAGGGAGCGGGAUGAUGGAGCGGGGAGCCAAGAUGAUGGAGCAGGGAGCUGGGAUGUUGGAGCAGACAGUUGGGAUGAUGGAGCAGGGGGCUGGGAUGAUGGAGCUGGGGGGCCCAAUGAUGGAACAAGAAGCCAGACUGAUAGAACAGAGGAAAUGAUCUGAGAAACAACUUUGAAAGGUCACCUGCAGCCCCCUGAUGCUUGCAUUAUGUUAAAAUGUUUGAAAAUUUAGAAUCCUCAUUUUAAGGCAUUGAUCUUUCCUUCAGAAAGCUGUCCUUGCUGUUAAACGGUGUCCGGAGAGUAAGGAGAUGGUCAGCACUGAGCAUUUAGUUUCUUCAGAGGAAUGACAGUGGGGGUUACUCUGUUUUUACUUGGAGUAUCUGGAUUGUUCAGGACCAAGUAAAACUCUGUAAGAAAGGGUUGGAAAUCCUGGUGGGCCUCUGUUAGCCCUUCCAAUAGAAGGGGGCCGGAGGGGGCCCACUGUCUGUGUCCUUGGACCUGCAUGCAAGCUGAAGGAAAUGGUGCCUGCUGCACAUGGAGGAGCUGGAGCCGUGGACAGGCCUGAGCUCAUCUCCAUCAGCACCCGGAUGUUGGCGUACAUGCCUGUGAAGGUGAGGGUCUGCACUUCCAGCAGCCCUCCCCCUUUGUAUGUCACUUUGGACACCCGAGAUUUCCCUGAUUUGCCUGGAGCCUCUGUGUAAUUUUUAAUUUGAUCCCCUGCGUCCCAGUGGACUGUGAGUGUCUUGAGGCCAGCACAGGCUUGGCCCCUCCCACAGCAGGGAGACAGUGGGGAGCCAGGCUAACAUGGGCCCAGGGAUGUAUAUUCUGGAAGGAGGGCAGGCUGGGGGACGGUCACGCCAAUAUCAGAGUGUGAAGUGGGGCUCCAUGAGAGGUGAGUCCUCAUCAGGAAGGGCCGAGGAGGGGACCUGUGGGCGAGGCCUGUUGACCAGAAUGAUCCAGUGUGGCAGAAGGCUGUCUGGGCUUGGAGAAGAUCCUGUGCAGAGAUCCUGGGGCCAGAAUGAACUUGGCAUGUCUGGGCAACCAAAGGAGGAGGGCAAGCUGGUGAAUGGGACGUGAGGUCAGAGAGACAGCCGGGGGAUGGUGAGCAUUUAGGAUCUGAUUUUGUCUGCCCUGGCACUUCCUGUGUCUGGCUCAGCACCGAGACGUUGCUAGGUGAGGGAGAUGAGGCUGAGACUGGUGGGCUCGGGGGAGAAUGGCUGAGAGCCAGGGUUGUGGAGGGUCUGCCACAUGGGGGACCAUGCCUCACAGGUUCAAGGCAUCCCUGGCCCCUGGCUCCCUCCUACUCUCCUUCAGCUGUUUGCCUGCUGGGUGACUCAGCUAUGGGCUACCAAGUCAUUUUGCCCUUUUCUGCUGGGAUCUGCGUGCUGAGUCUCUGACUGGUAACAUGCUGUGGUUUGGCAGCAUGCUUGGGAGUUGACAUCAUUUCUGGGUGCAAGUCUGGCUUUUUCUCCCUGGUGCAGGGUGAACAUGGGAUUAGGGGAGACAAGAAUGUCUGCUUUUUCGUCCAGACAUGCUGCCUUGCUCUUGCAGCUGAACAGACCCCAGCUGUAUUUGUAAGUUAAGCCCUUAAAUCCUGUGCCCUAAAGGUGGAGGUGCCAUUUCAUCUCCGAGAAGUGGAGAAAGAUUGUGCAGUGAUGCUGAGGUACAGGAGAGAGCUGAUGAGGAAUAGAAUGAUCAGUUGUUUGUAAGCAAUCUCCUCUCUUCUGGCUCUCUUUAGCAAAAGUUUUUAUUAUUAACUCUCCUUUCACCACUGCGGAUGGCAGACAUACCUGACGGCAAAACUGAAGCAUACCCUGACAGUGACCCUGUGGGGCAGACACACCUGAAUGUGUGUUUGGAGUUUUGAGCUAAGGAAUCCGGGAGUGGCCAACCUGGAGAUUCAUUCCUUGUUUAUGAGGAACAUCUGAGCCCCUAUCCUGUCCCGUGGAACACUGGGCAUACAGAUGAGCGAGGCCCUUUGUUUUGGGUUAAAUGAAGGUUGCCCCGUGGAGGCUGUUAGAGGAUGCUAGGUGGAAACUCUAUUUAUAAACCACAGGCUUCAAGCAGUUGCAGUUUUCCUGCCCAGUCCACUGCCACUGGGCCAUCCCUGUGUACAGGUUUCCCACUCGUAAGCCCCUGUGUCUCAUUUGCUGGCUCUGGGUCUCCUUCAGCUUCUUGGACCUGGUGCCGUCCCUGUAGGAGUUCAUUAGGGGUCUGGCAUGAUCCAGUUCAUCACUGGAAAAUGGUUCUGAAUGUAGGCGGUAAUGUUUGUGAUUGUCUAGGUUGAAGUCCGGGGCAGUCUACCUGUUUAGGCAAGAUGCAGGAUUAGGCAUCUGAGGUUCUCUUAUUCAUUGCAUUUUGGAUCUUCUGGAGCUCCUCCUGGCUGGUUAUUUUAAUGCUCUAUACCUUAGCCAACCACUUACAGAACUGUUUUGAUAGGCCACUGACUUCUGGUGUAGACGUUGGGGGUGAAGGAUGUUUGACAGAUGGGACGGAGAUGGAUUUAUGUUUGUGAAAUGUUGGGGAAACCCGAGGCAAUACCUGGAGCCCAGAAGAGUGGGCUCACCGUAUGUCCACAGCUCUAUCAGUGCCCCUAAGGUGAUUGGAAACUGCUUGCUGACCUGCCUGGUUAAGGAACGAACUCGGGUUCCACCAGAAACGUGCUGAGAGAUUUCCGUCCACCUUCAUGGAAUUCACAGAACAAAUGACAAGAUUUUAAUCCAGGUCUUGGUAUUCCUAGGGUGCCAGAGGUGAAACUGAGAAAAUUUUGCUCUCAAUUAUUUGGCGAGUUUGUAGGUAGAGAAUAAUACGAGCUCCUGGAGGGCUGGAAUCUGGAGGCAUUUCAGCAAGGGUUUAGAAAGGGUGGGUGAUGGUGACUAGGGAUACAGCACGUUGCUCAGCUCUGGGCUGAGAGGUGGUUAGUUCAGCCUGACGACCCAGCAGAGCACCUCCUGGUCAUUCUGCCGGCCCUUUAUCUGGUGAGGUAGGGCAAGGAGGGAGUUGGAGUGAGGAAAAAUGCCUAAGUCAAGGGAAUAGAGGGAGGGCAAGAUAAGAGAUGGCCCUUGUGCGAGAACUGUCUGCAUUGCUCACUCUUUGGAGAUUGAUGCUUUCUCCAUUUUACAGUUUUUAGGGGGAUGUUCUUACUGGCAAAGGAGGAAAACAGCUGUAAAGUGAGCAGUUUUUUUUUCCCCCGUGUGUUAAGGGAAUUUAUUUUCCUUUUCAUUCUUUGUUCCUCCUUGGCUCACCCCUGCUCAGGACAUAACUUUUGCAGAAAUGAGGAUUUUGCUGCAGCCUGAAUCUCCUGGGUUGGAUCUCUUAGAGCAAUUAAUAACUUGUUAUUCAUGUGUUCGGGGCACAGCCCUUUGUACUCAGUGGUGCGUCCGUCAUGCUGUUUGUGCUAUUGGGGACCACUAAGAGUGCUCUAGAAAGUUGGUGUGGGCAGUGCUGAGCUUUGGAGUCAUGGAGUGGCUCAGGUGUCAGCCCUGCCACUUACCUGUGUGCCCUUAGACAAGUACCUUUCUAUGUCUCUGUUACUCCUCUACGAGAUGGAGUUUAUCACAGGGUUUACUGCAUGAAGCUGUCACAAGGGUUCAACAAGAUGUUGCCUGGUGAGCACUUAACCCACACCAGGCACGUAGGGAGAAAGAGCUCAGUAGAGUGUGUGUGGGAGGGGUCUUCUUCCAUCCCAGGGAGGGAGGUAUUUCACCUGGGAAGGUCCUGGCUGGGAGCUGUCUUCUACCCCUUCUUUAUGCAGCGGGCUCUAAGCCAGCAUCUGGCACCGCCCUUUCCAAACCAGUGCACACUCUCCCCAUAGGGAAGGGGCCUGGCCUGCUGGGGCAUGCUUAGUUUCUGUAUUUUAAGAGCUCCCUCAUCUGAUGACCGGUACUAAUUACCGAAUUUCACAAAUGAAAUAUGUGCAGGGUGAAGGAAUAUGCCUGUUGAUUGCACUCGAAUUACUGCAGUAAAAUUAAAUUUCAAGGACUGCAGGAGCCUAAGAUCCUUCUGCUGUCCUCCACUUCCCCCAUCUUAAUUGGUUUUCCUUGCCAUCUGUCUUUCUUGCCUUUACUCCCCCAUAACUGCCAGCCCGCACUGUUAACCAGCGGUUUUCAAUCUGGCUGUACGUUAGGAACACCUGGGGAAAACUUUGAGCUGUAGAUGCCUAUCACCCACCCUAGACUGAUUCAGUCAGAAUGUCUGGCUGUGGGGCCCAAGUGUGUUUUAGAAAAAGCUCCCCAUGUGUGAAUGACUCUCACGCAGUCAGGUCUGGGGACAGCUGGUUAGGAAGGCGUCGCUGAGAGUCUCCAUCUUUUGGGAGUAACUGCUGAUGGUCAUGGAGCCCUUGAAUAUCUGUUUGGACUUUUUGAGGGCUCUGAGCUUGAGCUUGGUCUUCUCUUUUGGAAUACUUGGGUGUUUGCUUUAAUAUUCAGAGUUAAAUAUUGAUGGGCAUAUAAUGAAAUGCCUACUGGAUUACUGGACGAUGCUUUUAGCUAUGAGUACUUACUCUGGAAGCUCUGAGAAUAAUAAAAACGAUGAACAGCAGAUAUUAAGUGACAGUUUAGAACAGAAGAAAAAUACAAGUUUUCUUACAGGCUCUUGGCUAAAUGAAUAUGGGGGUGGACUGGGGUAUUCAGUAGUUGAGCAAUCCUGGAUUCUAUUUUUCCAUAUUUGCAUCUCCCCCCGCCCCCAAUGUUUUUGCUUUAUUUAACAAUUUUUGGGGUAAAAACCAUGUAACAUAAAGUUUACUGUCUUAACCAUUUUUAAGUGUACAGUUUUGUAGUGUUAAGUGUAGUCCUGUUGUGAAACUUUGUCAUCUUGCAGAUCUGGAACUCUGUAUCCAUUAAACAGUAACUCCCAUUCUCACCAGCCCCUGGCACCCACCAUUCUGCUUUCUGCCUCUGUGCACUUGACACCUCUAGGUGCUUCAUGUAAGUGGAAUCUUGUAAUAUUUGUCCUUUUCUGAUUGGCUUGUUUUCACUAGCAUGAUGUCUUCAAGAUUCAUCUCUGUUGUUCUGUGUGACAGGGUUUUUUUUUUAAUUCAUUUUUAUUGAGGUGAAAUUCAUGUAACAUAAAAUUAGCCAUUGUAAAGUAUACAGUUCAGUGACAUUUACUACAGUUGUACAGCUACCACUUCUGUCUAGUUUUUUUUUUUUUUUCUUUGAGACAGAGUCUUGCUCUGUCACCCAGGCUGGAGUGCAGUGGCGCUAUCUCGGCUCAGUGCAAGCUCCGCUACCCAGGUUCACCCCAUUCUCCUGCCUCAGCCUCCCAAGUGGCUGGGACUAUAGGGGCCUGCCACCAUGCCUGGCUAAUUUUUCAUAGUUUUAGUACAGACGGGGUUUCAUUGUGUUGGCCAGGCUGGUCUUGAUCUCCUGACCUCAUGAUCCACCUGCCUCAGCCUUCCAAAGUGCUGGGAUUACAGGUGUGAGCCACCGCGCCCGGCCACUUCUGUCUAGUUUUAAAACAUUUUCAUCCAAAUGGAAACCCUAUGCCCAUUAAGCAGUUGUUCCCCAUUUCCUCAUCUCCCCAGUCCCUGGCAACCACUAGUGUACUUUCUGCGUCUGUGGAUUUAUCCAUUCUAGAUAUUUCGUAUAAAUUGACUCAAGCACUGUGUGUCCUUUAGUGUCUGAGUUCUUCCACUUGCCAUAGUUUUUGAGGUUCAUUCAGGUAGUGGCAUGUAUCAACUUUCCCCCCCGACAGUUUUUAUUAUGGUAAAAUACAUAUAACAAAACUGACCAUUUUAACCAUUUCUUUCUUUCUUUUUUUUUUUUUUUGAGAUGGAGUCGCUCUGUGGCCCAGGAUGGAGUGCAAUGGUGUGAUCUCGCCUCACAGCAACCUCCGCCUCCCGGGUUCAAGCGAUUCUUCUGCCUUAGCCUCCUGAGUAGCUGGGACUACAGGUGCACACCACCAUGCCCGGCUGUUUUUUGCGUGUGUGUGUGUGUGUUUUUAGUGGAGAUGGGGUUUCGCCAUGUUGGCCAGGCUGGUCUUGACCUCAAGUGAUGUGCCCACCUCGGCCUCCCAAAGUGCUGGGAUUACAGGUGUGAGCCGCAGUGCCCAUAACCAUUUCUAAGUGAACAGUUCAGUGACAUUGUGUUCACAUUGUUACCACCAUCCGUCUUUAGAACUCUUUUCAUCUAGCAAAACUGAUACUCUGUACCCAAAAAACAGUAACUCUCCAUUCUCCCUCCCUGCAGCCACUGGCGGCCAGGGUUCUACCUUCUGUCUCUGUGAAUUUGACUCUUCUAGGUAGCUCAUGUAAGUGGAGUCAUUCAGUAUUUAUCCUUUUGAAUUGGCUUAUUUCACUUAGCAUAAUACCUACAAGGUUUAUCCAUGUAGCAUGUGACAGGAUUUCCUUUCUUUUUAAAGCUGGGUAAUAGUUCAUUCUAUGGACAUACAACGUUGUGUUUAUACAUUACGCUGCUAACACGUGCAACACAUUUGCUAUUCAUCCUACUGUGAACACAGGUGUGCACAUUUCCCUUCGAGACCCUGCUUUUCAUUCUUUUGGGAGUACACCUGGUGGAACUGCUGGAUCAUAUGGGAGUUCUGUUUUUUAAUAUACUGAGGAACCUCCAUACUGCUUUCCACAGUGACUACACCAAUUUUACAUUCCCACCAACUGUACACAAGGGUUCCAGUUUCUCCACAUCCUCACCAAUACUUGUUAUUUUCUGUUGUUUGAUAGUAGCCAUCCUAAUGGAUAUGAAGUGGUAUCUUGUGAUUUUGAUUAUCAUCUUUUUUUUGGAUGAGGGAAAGUUUGACCCCAUAUGUGGGUGUCUGUCACCAAGAUAGAAUGAAUGUAAUUUCCAAGGAAAAAUAAUCCCAGGCAACCUCUUCUGGAUUAUGUCCCAACUGAUUGGAAAUGCUGGGAACUUUCUGUGGUUGAAGGACCUUGACAUUUGUUGUCAAACUGCCUGUGAGUCACUUAUCUUCUGGGGGAAAAUAAACAUAACCGUGUCUUCCAGUCUGAAGUGGGGUGGGUGGGUGAUAUGAAGCAUUGCACACAGCAGAGCCUGCUGCCCCUCCACAGCCUCUGCAAAUGCCGUGUGAAGGUGGUGGACCUGCUACCAGAACUGGUGUCCUGCUGUCUCUGUAGUUAACUCUUAGGAGAAAUAACGGUUGUGUGUGUGGAGGUGAAGAAUGGGAAGGGAAGGAGGGGUGGGGAGGGCUGGUGCUUCUGAGGUUCCCAAAGUUCCUGGACUCGAAUUUUCUGUUGGCAAAUAAGCUGGUCAGAACUUAGGAAUGUGGUAAGUUGAUCCAGGAAGAAGUUGAAGGUUUCUAUCUGUGUUUUUCUGUGCGGUUGUGUAUGUGUAACACGUUUGCAGAAAUAGUUGAAGCUUAUUAUUUUCUUCAAAAGAUCUUAUUUUCUAGUGUGUAAAUCACAGGUAAUUAAAUAUGAGUUAAAGUAAGAGAGAGACCCUUGGGCUAUCUCAGACUUAGCUUUGAGAGAGAGAAUGAUCAUGGGUCUAAGGCAUCACUCUUGGUUUUAUAGGUUUGGAAACUCAAUGUUAUUAGUUCCAUCUAGGAGUUAUCAAUGGGGGAUUGGGGUUUACAUGCAUCAGAAUUGUAAGAUACUGCUAAGAAUGACAGUUCAUUAAUUGAUGAGAACUGUGCCUCGCUGAGAAAGCCAGCACUCCUGGGGUGUGUGUACUCCGCAGACCUUUUCUUUUGUUUGUUUCUUUCUUUCUUUUUUUUUUUGAGACGGAAUCUCUGUUGCCCAGGCUGGAGUACAGUGGCACGAUCUCAGCUCACUGCAGCCUCCGCCUCCUGGGUUCAAUCUAUUCUCCUGCCUCAGCCUCCCAAGUAGCUGGGAUUACAGGUGUGUGUCACCACAUACUAAUUUUUUGUAUUUUUUUUUUUUUUAGUAGAGACAGGGUUUCACCGUGUUGGCCAGGAUGGUCUUGAUCUCCUGACCUUGUGAUACGGCCACCUUGGCCUCCCAAAGUGCUGGGAUUACAGGUGUGAGCCAUUGUGCCCGGUCCUCAGCAAACCUUUUCUAUCGGCCUAUUUCUAUCUAUUUUCUAUCGGCCACCUUUUCUAUUGGCCUAUUUCCAUCUGUCUGAGGAAUCUUGAUGCAUCGGCCUUCUCGUUCUGGGGAUCUUUCUGUGUAUAGAAUCAAUACCCUCUCCUUAGGGUAGUGAUGGAGAUUGAUUUUUCAAAAAUCCCAACAUGUAAUUUAUGAAAUUAUUGUUUCAGCUCCAGACUCUGUGCUCUGUUCUGCAGUGUUGGAGCUAGGACCGCACAUCCCAGCUGCUUUGCCAGUGGCUUCCGGGCCACCUCCAUCAGCAGGAGGCGGUAGAAGCACCAGCAAGAUGGGGCUUUGGUCCUUCCUGUUGGCUUCCUGUUGCCCCAGCUGUAGCUGUUGAAUUCAGUCUUCAGUUAUCCCAGCACUGGCCAGCCAGCCUCAUCGUCCACACUCCCUGCAGAUCCCACCACUCCUCCAAGGAAGUCUCUACCUCAGGGCCCUUUGGCUACGCUUCUAAGGUUAAGUCUAACCGGUUCCCUCAGGCCUAGGGGUGGUGGCUGCUUCCUGUCGUUGCUACUUCCCUGAUAUCUAGAAUUUUCCUUUUUCUACCCAGUUACCUGGUUACUGACUUUCUACCCAGUUAACAAUUUAUAUUAAAGCCCUUCUGUUCAAAAAGCUUAUGUAGUUUCUGCGUUCUAAUUGGAUCCUGACUAAUACAUCUGACUUUCAACAUUCUUUAGUAAUCAGUCAGCAAAAUGAUUUCAUGAGAUAGACGUAUUAUAUUUAAUUGGAUUACAGUUCACCUUAUAUUCCUUUAGUUUUUUUUUUUUUUUUUUUUGCACUGAUCUUUCUGAUUUUCGUUAGGCUCGUCUAUGUAAUUUGAGACAUAACUCCUCUCAUUAGCUACUUUCUAAAUCAUCAGACUUGAGUUCUUUCCUGGAAAGAUCACCACAGAUGGCUAAUGUCAUUCAUUUUGUUGGCUCUUUUGGCUUUAUAGUAGAGGGUGACAAUUCUUUUGUUUUUGGUUUUUUUUUUUGAGCUGGGGUCUUGCAUGACCUCACUGCAACCUCUGCCUCCCGGGUUCAAAUGAUUCUUCUGCCUCAGCCUCCUAAGUAGCUGGGAUUACAGGCACGCGCCACCAAGCCUGGCUAGUUUUUGUAUUUUUAGUAGAGAUGGGGUUUCACCAUGUUGGCCAGGCUGAUCUCGAACUCCUGACCUCAGGUGAUCUGCCUGCCUCGGCCUCCCAAAGUGCUGGGAUUACAGGUGUGAGCCACCGCACCUGGCCAAGGGUGACAUUUCUAAACCUUAUCUCUAAAUUCUGUGUCCAUUAUUCAGUAUUCCUUUAACUUGUAGAGCAUGGCUAUUACGUGUUUAAGCAACAUAUAUCUCUAAAAAGAUUCGAGGCCGCUUAUAAGAGAAAGUAUAUUAUGUGUAAGCACAGAUUCAUUAAAAUAAGAGUUUAAAAAUCUGGGGUCAAAUUUAGGGGGUAGAGGGGAUGAGGGAUAAAAAGGUGAAGGAAAAAAGAAGUGGAUGGAGAAUUAAAGAAUGAAGGAGAAUUAACACUGAACACCCACCCCCAUGGAGCCGGAUCCUGGCUAGGUGUUUGCCAUCUGUGUUUAGUUUAAUGCUCAGCAUAAUCCUGCGUGGCAGGUAUGUUACCCCCAUCUAUAGGUCAAGAACCUGAAACCCAAAGUGCUGGCCGAUUGUGCUCUAGUCCCCCUAUACAUUUCAGCUUACGUCUACUGACACUAAGCCAAGGGGAGCUCCUUCAGUUGAACGUGCAAUUGUAUCUUGGUAGCCAAAGCAAGAAAGGAAGCAUGUUGGGUUGCAUAGUUCUCAUUUGAUAAUACAAUGAAACAUUUUCUUGAGAGAGAGAAACAUUUUCUUAGCCUUCAAGCUUGAUAAGAAUCUAGUGGAUAUUAACUUAAAGGGCACUGAACAUGAUAAUAGUGUCCGUCAGGGGGAGAAAUAACAGAAACCAAAAGCAGAGAUGCACACGUGGCCGUUUAUUUAAAUCAAACCUGAAGCAGAAGGAGGAGCAUUAGAUCACAGUUGUGUAAAGGCAAUUCUAGGAGAAAACGAUGGACUGUAGCUAGCUUUCUGCAGUCCUGACCUGGCCAAGGGUAAAACUAGAUCGGCUGCGGGCUGUGUUCCCUGGGCUUCCUGCUGCUUCACUCCUGGGAGGCAGCACAGAGUGGUUGUUACGGGGAAGGUUUUCAUAAGUGCUGUGAAUCCACCCUGGGCCGUUUACUGGCCUUGCACAUGUGGGCAAGGUACGGUCAAGCUCAGCAUGAUGACAUUUUAGCCAAUGACAGAUCGAAUACCCAAUGGUGGUCUCAUAAGAUUAUAUACUGUAUUUUUACUGUACCUCUGUGUUUAGAUACACAAAUACUAUUAUGUUAUAGUUGCAUACAGUAUUCAGUACAGUAACAAGCAGUCCAGGUUUGCAGCCUAGGUGUGUAGUAGGCUAUACCACCUCGUUUUGUGUAAGUGCAUGCUAUCAUGUUGCCACAAUAAUGAAAUCACCUAAGGGCACAUUUCUCAGAAGGUAUCCCUGUCAUUAAGCAACACAUGACAGUACUUAAUCUCUCUAAGCCUUAGCUUCAUCCCUUCUUAAAUGAGGGUAAUAAUACUGUUUCGUCCACCUGUGUGUGUGUGUUUGAGAUAGGGUCUCGCUCUGUUGCCCAGGCUGGAAUGCAGUGGCACAAACAUCACUGCAACCUCGAUCUCCUGGGCUCAAGCAAUCCUCCUGCCUCAGCAUCCUGAGUAGCUAAGAAUACAGGUGUGUGCCACCAUGCUGGCUAAUUUUUUUUUUUUUUUUUUUUUUUUUUUGGUAGAGAUUGGGUUUUGCUAUGUUGCUCAGGGUGGUGUCAAACUCCUGGCUUCAAGUGAUCCUCCCACCUUGGCCUCUUAAAAUGCUGGGAUUACAGGCAUGAGCCACCAUGCCUGGCCUUAUUUUUAUAUAUUUAAGAACAUAUGCUUUCGGCCGGGGUGGCAGCUCAUGCCUGUAAUCCCAGCACUUUGGGAGGUCGAGGCGGGUGGGAGGCGGGUGGAUUACCUGAGCUCAGGAGUUUGAGACCAGCCUGGCCAACAUAGUGAAACCCCCCUCUCUACUAAAAAUACAAAAAAAUUAGCCAGGCGUGGUAGCAGGCACCUGUAAUCCCAGCUACUUGGGAGGCUGAGGCAGGAGAAUCACUUGAACCCGGGAGGCGGAGGUUGCAGUGAGCUGAGACUGCAUCACUGCACUCCAGCCUGGGCAACAAGAAUGAAACUCCGUCUCAAACAAAAACAAAAACACCAUAUGCUUUCCCAACACAUCUGGACAGCUGAUAUUAAAAAAGGGUGUAUGUAGUAGAAUUAAAACUAUUACAAGAGAAACAGAGCCAGACAGUUUGGGGAAGGGAGAAAACAGAGAGGUUGUGGGGGCACUUACCUUGAAUCUUCUUAGGUCCCUUGUGUGUUGUUUUGCCUAAUCCUUCCCACACGUCUGCAAAGAGGAUGAUCUCCCCACGUAGAGACAGGAAGCGGAUUCCGAUACCUCGCCUUCCCUGUGUUAGAUGUGCCGUAGCUCCUACUGAGGGUGAGGAUUAAUUGGAGAUGAUGCAAGUGGACCUCUAAGCACGGGCCGCGAUGAUGUCGUAGUUCACGGUCACAGGACUGUCACUGCUGUUACAAACUGGCCCUUCUGCUCCGAGUCUGCUGGUCCUCAUACGGUUCCUUUCUGUCUCUGGUUGUGUUGGUUAAGACAGAGUAGCUGCAAUCAGGGAGAGUGUCGACCCUGACCCCAACAAGCAGGGAGAGCUAGUGCAGAAUGUGGGCAGUGGCAGCAGACCCGCGGGGCUGUGACACUGUCCUUUCUGUGGCUUGGGUGGACUUCAGGGUGACCCAUCUAGCAGAGUAAAAAUAGUAACCCCACAUGCUGACCAUGUACCCCCUGCUUUCACGCACUUUUAUGGGUGAAUUCACCUAUCCGUUAUAGAAACUCCAUGAGGCGUUUUUAUUAUCCCCAUUUUACAGAUGAAGCUGUCAGGGAGAGAGGUUGAGUUGCCGGCAGUCUCACAUGUAGAAGUGGUGAAGUGGGAAUUCAGACCCACCCCUGCGGGCUCCUCAGCCAGGCCUGCUCUUAGCAUCCCAGUGUGCUGCUCUGUGACGAGCCCCAGUAUUGGGAUCCACUCUCCAGAUGAGGUUUGAAGAGUUCCGAAGUGGAACGUCUUUCUGGGUUGGCUGGCUGUAGAGGGGUUGGUGACUCCAGUGUCCUGUGGUGGUAGACAGUCUCCAGCCAAGGGCAUGUACUUCUCACCUCCCUGCCUCGUGAAUCUGGUCAGUCUGGUGUCAAACUUGAACCAGUAGACUGCUGUGGAUGUGACACUGGGCGUGGUGCAGGCUCUGUCCUUGAGGGGCCUGGUAGCCCCACCUGGGUCCCCUGGGGCCCAACUGCCAUGCUAGAAGACGUCCAGGCUGCUCUGCUGGAGAAAGAAACCGUGUGGGGUUGCCUGGAGGGUGAGACAUGUUGGAGGGGAGGGAGGGAGAGGCCAAGGCCUCAGACAGGUGAGAGAGCCCCAGCCGCGAGGCACCUGUGGUCUCACCAUGGGACAUAAGAACUUGUUUAAGCCAUGACGUUUUGGGAGGGCUUUUGUGCAGGAAUGGCACCCGGAACUCCUGCUUCCCAUGAACCCAGGGCUGUGGGCCUGGCUGCUGGGAGUGAGCCAUUUGCUGGGCCAGGGAUUUGCCCUGCUGCAGGGACUUUUCUAACCCAGCCGGGCCAGGCUCACCUGGGGGCCCUUUUGAUUUUGAGAGGACGCAUACCUCAGCCUGCAUUUUGGUGUCCUCUUGCUAGCACCUGCCAGCUGAGGUUGAGCCAUGGUGGACAAUUUUUCCUUUUAAGACGAUUCUAGUUACUGAACCAAAGAUAUUAAUUAUGUGCUUAUCUGUGGUAAUUACAACUAAAGCAUUCUUUAUCACUGCAGCUUAGUCAUUUGCUUACGUGAUUUAAAUGUGAUAUAUGUUAAUAUGCAUAUCUCGUCAAAGGGAGUCAUGGGGGUGGCAUGGUUAGAGCAUGCUGGCUGAGGGCAGGAGGCCAGAGGUGUCUGCGUCUCCCUCGUCCAUCUCGUUCUCCCCUCCCGCCUUCCUUCCCCUUUCCCCUCUCUCCCUUCUUUCUGUCCCACCAGGAUUUCUUUAAGGUUUGUGUUUCAUCACCAUCAUCCUGUUUGAAAGUUUUUUUUUGUUGUUAAUCCAUCAGUCUUUCUCAAUUCAUAAUUAAUUUCUUCCAACCUCCCUCCCUGCUCCCAUCCUUGGCAGCCUGGGGGCAGCAGGUUGGGAACUACCACCAAUGUUGCACCUUCUUAAUAUUCUUUUAUGUAUCUCUUCUCAAAGAUAGAAUUAGUUUGGUCUGAAUUAUACAUACAAUCAUAGAAUCAAAGUGACUUGAAACUUAGAAGGUGCAUUUUCUUUUAGGGUUUAAUUCACUCAGAGGUCCUCCAACCCAGCCUCUCAUUCAGUAAAGACUUCCCUUCAGCAACAGAUGGUAAAUAGAUUCUGCAGAAUGAGUAAUUCCUUCAUUUCUGUCUGAAUGGUUUGUUUAGAAGCAAACACAAUGAUUCCCUCUCCUUAUUAAAUUUGUUGGGAGAACAUCAGGAUCAUACUAAGUUACUGUCCAAAGCUACAACUGUGAAGAGGGGGUGCACGGUGACAAAAAAGAGAAAUGUCGCUUGACAUUUCAGAAUUCAGGCCCAGUAUCAUCGGUGCCCUCAUAACAUUACACGCCAAACCCUUUAAUAAAACUGUCAAUCCAGAUUGUUAAAACACUGAGCGGUUUGCUCAGGAGAUAGAAUAUUUAUCAUACUGAGGUUCCCAGUUUUUAAUGAGCCAAAUAUAUUUCCUUAUUUUUUUCAUGAUCUUUAAUUUAUCAACUUAACCAUUUUUAAGUGUACAGGUAAGUGGUAUUAAGUACAUUCAUAUUAUUGUGCAGCCAUGUCCACCGUACAUCCACGGAGCUCUUUCAACUUGCAGAACUGAGACUCUGUGCCCAUUAAACACAACUCCCACUCCCCACUCUCCCAGCUCCUGGCAACCACCAUUCUACUUUCUGUCUCCGAAUCUGACUACUCUAGAUACUUCUAUUAGUGGAAUCAUACAGUAUUUGUCCUUUUGUGACUGGCUCAUUUCACUUAACAUAAUGUCCUCAAGAUUCAUCCCUGUUAGAGCGUGUGUCGGAAUUGCCUUUUGAAGGCUGAGUAAUAUUCCAUUUUGGAGGCUGAGUAAUAUGUACAUGUGCACAUUUUGUAUAUCCAUUUAUCUGUCAGCUGACUUUUGGGUUGUUUCCGCUUUCUGGAUAUCAUGACUAGUAAUGCUGUUCCUCACAUUUUAACAUUCAAAUGACACAUCAUAAUUUCAUUUAUUCUUGAUAUCUCAGGAAAAUUUUAAAUACCGUUUAAUAGUGGAGAAUUAUGGUAACACGCACCAAAUGUACAUUAUAUUUUUAAUUGCUUGGCAAUUUGGGACAACUUACAAAUUCUGUCUUUAGGUUUGGUCGCUAUACAACAGAUAAUGCUGCUAUUUCUGCUUUAGUUUCAGGGAUCAAAAUGAGUUAAUACGUAUGAAUGUCCUUUGUAAAGAGAGAAUGUAAAUGUUUGUCGAUAGAACCAGAAUACAUUCUGAACUUUCUUGCUUGUAUUCUGGGUAGGUAGACAUUUAAAGUAGAGAUUUGGCAUAACUUAGUUCUUCCAGAAACUUCAAGCACUUUACACUCACUCUUUUUAGCCCAGGUUUGAAUUAUGUGGGGUCAUUCAUGGGGUUUAUGAGGUUUGAAGACAUACUUAAAUAACAUGUGGGUUCUCUAGAAUGAAUGUGGAAGGAAACAUUGUACUCCUGUGGAAUGCUGGCACCCUAACAGGAGUGACUUUCUCUUUUCUCUCUCUUUUCUCCUUUUGGUCAACUCUGUUUGUAUGUAGUGUGAGCUCUAUACUGUGGGAUAGCAUUCUUUUUAGAAUGCAUGCAUGUGAAUUGUGUAGUGCAGAGAUUUGCUAUAUCCAUUUCCAGAAUGUACAUAUUGAACACUGUUUUGCGAAAGGCAGGUCUAUGCAAACUACCCCAAAGUCCGAGGAAGCUGAGAGGCUGAAGGAAGAGCCUGACAAAUCCCGUUUCUUAGAAAGAAACAUUUAAUAGAGACCUACAAGCAGAAGCCGCAUCUGUGUCUAGGGCAGCGGUAAGACGAGAUGGGGGAGCCCCACGCCAUUACCCCCCAGACCCAGGGCUUCUAUGCCAUAGCGGGGAGGGAGGAGUGGUUCCAAAGGGAUACGUAGGACAAUUGAAGUAAGAUAACAUCAAGGUUGUUUGAUCUGAGGGCAGGAUUUACUGUAAGCACCUGCUCUUACACAGGAAUAGUAGAUAAAUGGGAAGUCUUAGAGGCCUUCUUGGAUAGGGGGUUAAUCAGAAGCCAACGUGGCAGAUUAGCAUCCAAGAUGGAGUUGCUUUAGCCUCCACAAGCACUGACUGUAUGCCAGGAGUUGACCAUGAUGUGUUAUGAGGCACUGGGGAAUUCAUUCCUAUAUGAAUCUGGGUGAUUGACAAGAAAUUCUAGUGGAAGUGACAUGUAGGUUGAGCUGUGCAUUGAGCGGGCUGGUCACGUGCCCCCCUUUAGAUGUUCCCGAUCGCGCGGAAUCACGACAUGAGAGGAUGAGAUCAGAGUUCUGUCAGCUUCAUGUAGCCAAGGACUUUCAAGUUCUUCCUUGAGGAGUUGGCCCUCCCUAGUCUCCUCUGUUACACCAGUCAUUGCUACGUUAGCAGCUUUGCAAAGUAGGUAUCACGCUCCAUGUGCUCUGUGCCUGCUGUUGGCCUGAAGCAUUGUCAUGGCCUUGCCCAGGUUUGCUUUCCUUAAGGGCACCAUUUGGUCCCUUUUGUCAAACCCAUUUGCUUACACAGGCUGCUGCACUAUUUCUAUGAUUGCAAUUCCAGAGUUUCCGAGUCCCGGGAUGGGGGUGUCUGAUGUUAGUAGCAUGCCAUGGUCAGAUGUCUUGGGGAAUCUGGGGGUAAGCAUAGUUGAAUACACUCUCUGCUGCAAGUUUCUCAAAAAUGUGAAUACACCAAUGGUGUUUCAUGAAUCCACCAAGACCAUACAGCACUAUAGCUUUGCCUGGAGAGUUUUCUCUCCUCAGCAAAGCUCUCCACCUGUCCCAAGCUGUGAUUCCCAAGAAAUGCCAGCUGGGAAGCCUGGUUUGAGGGUAGCAUAUGCUCCAUUGCCAUGGCCAAGUCAGUACAAGCCUUUUAGCAAUGGUGCGUUCCCUCAGAAGGUUUGCUGUGGCCCAUUUAGCCAUAUUUUGGCUUUGGUUCCUGGAAGGGAGGUGUCUGCCUUCUUCCUAGUGGUGUGCUGCCCACCAGGCAUGCCCAGUGGCUCAUCUGUCUCUGCAGAUAGCUUGGCUGAACCCAAAAGGGCUCAGUCCUUCCUGUGGGCUUGAUGCCUGUAGGAAGGGCCAGUCUUGUCCCCAUGUCUGCAGUGUGCCACAGCCUCCUUUCCAAUUUGUUUCCAUUAUAGGAUUAUGAGACCUCCUGACUCUAAGGAACUGUUUUAUCUGGGGCUUGGUGUUGCGGGCACAGCACCUGUGAAUAGUUAAUGACAUUUUUUAUUCCCAACCAAGACCUAGGCUCCUUUAGGGCAAGGGCCAGUGUUGAUCUGAGGAUAUAUUCCCAGCUUCUCACACAGUCUGUGGUGCAGACUAGGAGUUCCAUAGAUCGUUGAAUGAAUGGUUUAAAAAAUGAAGGGAUCAAGUCCUGGAAGUGGUUUUAAUUUGCUGUGACUCCAGGUAGCUUGCUUAAACACUCUAUGUUUUCUAAAUUUUAAAAUAGAGCUAAUAUUUCUCAAAUGGCUCCAUAGGACAUUGGUGACACUCAGUUCUGCACCAGCUCUUUGCCUGGUAAUGUGCAGGAUGGGGGAUGCCCAGGGUAUCUUUUUAUUCCUUUUUUUUUUUUUUUUUUUUUUUUUUGAGAUGGAGUCUCGCUCUGUUGCCCAGGCUCCCAGGCUGGAGUGCAAUGGCGCGACCUCGGCUCACUGCAAACUCCGCCUCCGGGUUCAAGUGAUUCUCCUGCCUCAGCUUCCCGAGUAGCUGGGAUUACAGGCACCUGCCACCACACCCGGCUAAUUUUUGUAUUUUUAGUAGAGACAGGGUUUCACCAUGCUAGUCAGGCUGGUCUCGAACUCGCCACCUCAGGCGAUCUGCCCGCCUCGGCCUCCCAAAGUGCUGGGAUUACAGGCGUGAGCCACAGCACCCGGCGUUUUUAUUCUUAAAAUAAUCCUGUGAGGCGUAUGUAGUGUUCACCUGAUUUUGUAAAUGUGUAGGCACAGGGAACCGAAUAACUUGCUCAAGAUCACAAAGGCUUUAAGUUUGAGAAGUGCAGUGAAAAUGCGGGGCUGCUUCACUCCAAAGUCGAUGUGUGUAUAUGUACAUAUAAGUGUAUAUGCAUGUGUACAUGUACAUAUAAACAAAAGUACACAUUUAGGAAGUGUAUGGGAAAUAUACAUGUACACAUGCGUAUACAGUCAUAAGGACGUUUCAGUUAACAGUAGACUGCAUAUAUCACAGUGGUCCCGUAAGAUUAUAAUCUUGUAUUUUUACUGUAUCUUUUCUAUUUUAGAUAACAAAUACCAUUGUGUUACCUACAGUAUUCAGGACAGUCACAUGCUAUACAGGUUUGUAGCCUAGAAGCAGUAGGCUGUACCAUCUAGCCUAGGUGUGGAGAAGGCUGUACCAUUUAGUUUUGUGUAAGUACACUCUGAUCACACGAGCAAGAAAUAGCAUAAUGAUGCAUUUCUUAGACCAGAUCUCCAUUGUUAAGUGAUGCAUGACUGGAUAUACACAUACACAUAUGUGUAUGCCUGUAUAGAUGCGUGUAUUCUACAUACUCCUAAAUGUGUCAUAUGGCAAGGGUGCCUCAUUGUAAUUCUGGCUUUUUCCAUAAAUGUUAAACAAGCAUCUUCUCCCACCGCCAGUCCUUUUCUUCCUUCAAGGGGACAGGGCCUCUGGAGCUUAUGCCCAGCUCCUGUCGGAUGCCCCCGUGUUCUGGUCACUCGUGUGCCCGUCUCUUCACACUCAGUUUUCCCACCCCUGAGCACCUCAGGUGCCAAGGUGUGUUUGUUGAACUGAAAUUCUUAAGCCUGCUGAGUACAUUCUCAGUUUGUCAAGACAGAUAAACAAAUACCUUUUUUAGAUGAUUUAAAAGAUUCUUGACACAGUCCCAGUGGUGUUUUAACAACUUUUCAGGUCCUGAUCAGCCAAACUCUGGGCCAAAAGUAAAUGUUUAAUAAACAACAUAAGAGUGAUGGAGGAAAAAUGUAUCUUAAGUGGAACUGUGUGUUCUGUAAAUCUAUGACAGAUUACUGUUCCUGCUUUUGUUGUGUAUAAUUAUUCUUGUUCCUCCUGAGAAUUGCCCUCUCUUUCAUCAUGAAACGUAUAAGAUGGCCUCCUCCUCUGGUAAUUUGGAGCAAUUGGCCUGGGAGAGGAUUGAUGUGUAGUAAGGACAGUCCGUAGGAGAGAUUUAGUGGGGGCAGUUUCCUUAUCUUCUAUUCUGUCCCUUUGCCAGACAGAAGCACAAAAAGUAGUUGGACUGAAAAUGCUGCUUCCUAAAAUUAGCUCUCCUCUUUGUUUUCCGAAUGGUUUUACUGGUUGAUGCGGGCACAAUUUGCCCUUCUUGGGGAGCCUUCUGCAUUGUGUAAAGUGCAAAGACACAUCUAUCAGAGAAGCUAAUUUUAGGUGCUAGUAAGUUUUAAGGGCAUGCAAAGCUCAAAACUUUGCCUGUUCUCUUGGAAGAAGAUUUUUCCCUCCUGAAAAACAAGCUUCCUUUCAAAGUCAGAAAAGGGGAGCUUAGACGAAGCCCCAGGAGGGCAGGUAUGUCUUGUUCACUGCAGUCUCCAGUGCCUUGCGAGGGCCCGGCAUGCUGAGCGCUCAGUAACCCUUGGCCUAAUGUACAGUUUUUCAUUCUGUGAAUCAGGAAUAGAGCAACAUAAGGGGAGCUUCUGCUUGAGACAGCAAUGGCAGCAUCAAAAUAAACGUGGCAAUUUUGGUCUUCAAGAGUGAAGUUGUGUCUCUGAAAUUGUAAGCCCAAAUGGAUCAUUUCCUUUUUUAGGUUUUAGAAUUCCAGGUUUAUUUUCUGGAAGAGCUUGCAGCAGAUGGGCUUCUGUAGGGGAACGUUUAUACCUUGGGGGUUCCGUUUCGAGAGUCCUUGAUUUAUUAUUGUUUACAAAUGGUGGUUGGAAAUUGUUCAUUGAUUUGACAUAAAGCUGCCCAGGCUUAUUGUAAAAACACCUCUGCAUCCAAUUAGAAUGACAGACACUUAGUGUGAUGACUCAGGACAGUUGAUGGCCUUAAAAAAAAAGCGAACAGAUUAAAUCACUCUCUGUUUUUUCAUAGCCAUUGAUGGAAACAGAUUCUGUGGGGUAAAUAACAGAGUCUUGGGUGGUGGAAAGGUUGAAGAUGUCCAGUAGUUGUGGCAGGGCAAGGAUGGAGGACUUUUUCUUUGCAGGGGCAGUGGAGAGGCGGGGCCAUGGGUGAAGACUGGAGAAUACUCAGAAGGUAGCAUGGACGAGAGUGUUGUUUGAUGACUCUGCAUGUGACCAGUAGUGACAUUUUACUCACUGAGGCUCAUAUUGAGGUUAAGCCCGAGGUCCAUUGGCCUUGCUGAGAUCGUGUUUAGAACACAGCACUGUGCAGUAAGAGACUCCUAUAACUCUAUCAAAUUUGCAUUUGGAGGAAUUGUAAAGAGCCUCUGUUACCUCCUAGGUGAGGCAGUCCAGGAAAACAGUUGCUAGAAGGAGCUAUCUGCAGAAAUAGACAGUUGUGGUCCUUUCAUGUUUUAAUAAUUGUUCCCUGGAUUUCAAGGAGUCAGUCCAAAAUCCCCGUAAUAGAUUUUAGUAACGUUCAUGGAAUCUCAGUUUGCACAUCAUGAGACCUUUAGUGUGGUGUUUACUGUCUUCACCUUAAUAUACUUUGUAUCCAUGAGCAACCUUGCUACAGUCAUGCAAAGAUGAUUAUUUUUUAUUCAGCAAUAAUUAGCCACAGUGUUGAGCACCCAGAUGCCUUCCUGCAGCAGCCCCCCUUUUCUCCCCAGCCAACAUCUGCAACUGUGAACAGAUUUCCAUCUUCAGCCUUGGUGGUUGGAAAGAAAUGUAAGUCACCUUUUUUUCUGGUUGGUUCUGGGGCAGAUGCCACCAGGCUGCAGAGGCAGUCUGUGUCUGUGGGGCUCACCAGGGCAUGAGUUCUGCUCCCAGGAAAGAGAUUCUUGCAGGAUUUUGUCUGUGGUUCUAAGGAGACAAGUAGGUGGCACACAAAAACAGAAAAUGAAAGAACCCAUCCCUCCAAAACCACACACACAAAGCCAAAAGGAAAAAAAAAAAGCACAUAAUUAUCAUGUAGGCACUGUUGCAGCUAACCCUGAUUUUGGCCUCAAUUCUGAAACAAGUUAGCUGGUUUAGACAAACCCCUUAUUAGGUAAUGGAUUGUUAUUCAUUCCUCCCCUUCUCCUAGUCAUUUACUCCGUGAGAGCUGCUCCUACCUGACCUUCCACUGAUUUUGGUAGCAGCAUCUCCCAGAGCGACUGUUUCCUUCUUCAGCAGUGUUCCUUACUCAGGGUGUAAGAUCUUAACCCCACAGAGCCCCGUAUCAGGUUUAAUUAACUAAUUGAUUCAGCUUGUGCUUACUGAGUGCGAGGCAGUCAUGUGCUUCUGUUUGGUAAAUGGCUUCAUUUUCCCUCUAACUCCUGAGCGUCCUGAAGCUUCUCUUAUGGUUCUCUCCAAAGGAGUCAGCAGGCUGGCUCUGCAAGGGUCAGUAGGUUCUGGGGUGGUGGGGGGCCGAGGGAGGCAGGGAGGUUGGCUCUGUCUUUAUUUGGCAUAGAGCUCCCCGAACAGGGUCUCUCCUCCUUUCUCCAAAGGUUAAUGGAACCACUAUCUUAAAAAGCUGAAAUCUUAUCUUCUGGGGUAUUUGGGUAGAGAAGGCUAGGGAAUCCCUUUUCCAUGGUGGUGCAGUAGGUUCUCAGAACCAGCUGGUGGGCCUCAAAGAGAGGCGGCUGUAUUUUAGCCUGAUAAUCUUGAUUCCUGGUUUCCUGGCUCUGUAGCAUCAGAAAUGGGAAGCUUUAAAAGCCGUGCCUUGUUGGAUGCACCGAGUCAUAAAAUAAAUGUGAUGUGCUGGGUGGGGGAAAUGCGGGAGGAGGGAAACAGGUGGUUGGAGCUGCUUCGUGAUGGCCGCCCACCCUGGCUCUCCUUUCUUAAUAGGCUUCAGAAAUCCUGGAAUGCGUAAUUCACCAGCUCACAGAGUUCCACCCAUGUCCCCAGUGGCUUCAAAAUGUAAAUGACAUUUGCAGUGCUGGGAGGUAGGAGGGCGAUCCCGUUCCUUCCCUGGAUCUCAGUCGCAGAGGUGCUGGCUCAUGUGCCUGAGUGCAGCGGCUGGCCCGUCAUUACUGGUCUUUGCAGGAAGCCACUCUGAAGGCACCUGGGCCCUUGCCAGGCUGAGUCACAGCUGACUUAGGGAAAUGCCACACAGGACGCUUGCAGUCCCCCCGUUCUAAGCGUAGGUUUUGCAACUGCAUACUCGGAAAAUGAAUCAGAGUGGGGGAAAGUGUCAGAGAAACAGCAGAAAUGGAAUGUAGGCAGGAGGGCCACAGUGGCGCUGUGGAUUCAGACCACACCUUCGGCUCUGUUUGGGGCCCUUCCUGUAAGGAGCGUACUGAUGCCAGAGGCUGGGGGUGUGGAAGGGAAGCUGCUGUGCUGUUAGAUCCAUUCUGCUAUUUAGCCAGCCUUCCUUUUCCCAGCUGGCACAGACAGGAUGUGUUAGAGAGGUGCUCAGACCUCCUUUCAGAGCAACUGAAUCAUUCUCCAGGAGGGACAGGGAGUCUGAAAUGCAAACAGGUUCCCAGGGUUAUUGAAGAGCAGCCAAACUGAACACCCACUGCUCUGUGGACUCAAGCUGGUUUUAGACAUUGUUUGGUCAGGACCAGAGCCGAGCUCUGGGGCCCACUGGGGGCUCUUGUCGCACCAUAUCAUUGAUUCUACAAUGCACAUUUCCCCCGCCUCUCAUGUUUUAACAUGUCUGAAAUCAGGAUGCAUCUUCCAUGGAUGGUGUUUCAGGGUUUCAUUGAUCGUGUUUUUCUUCCUGAGUGGCACACAAAAUUAAUGGUGCUCCCUAGAGUUGAUGGUCCCUGCGGUUCAGUGAACCGUGUUGCUCUUGUGUAAGCUCCUGUGGGAACAUAGAGUCUCUGUGUCCCACCUUCUUCCUCGCAGUGGUCAGCACGGAUGAGGUGGGAGUUGCAUAAAUGUCAGCAUUCGAAAGUGAGGGCGUCUGUCGGUGCUGUCUCACUGUGGGGCUUCAGAGAACGUGAGCACCUGUGUUUGCAUUCUCCAUCAAGGUUCAUGUCCUGUUGGCUCAUAAGCAUGAUUAUAUCCAUUAUACAAACUGGGGCACAGGCACCCAGAGAGAAGUCAAAAGACUUGUUCAAGAUGGACAACUAGGAAGUGGUGGGGACAGACCAGUCCUGUCUGAUGCCAGAUCCAGCGCUGUAUCUGCCAGUCAGCAUGCACACUUUCAUCUCUCCAGCCUCUUCCCACUCACCUUUACUCAACAUUUCUGGGCCUCCAUAGUGAUUGUAGUAAUUCGGUAAAGAUGAUUCAUUUCUUUAGUCCGGUCUUCGGACUUGACUUCUUAGAAGCAGGUCUUGUGCAAUAGUUGCAUAUUAACCACUUGGUGACACAGUGCAUGAGGGUAUGCCAACUCUUUUUGCUCAUGGCCGUGCAGUGCAGAAUUUCCAGGCAUUGUCCGCUCUGUUUCCUGGACUUCGGAGUGAUAGCAAAGUUUUGUAUUCCCUGAUCAGCUGUGUAUCUCUGAGCAGCAAGUUGAUCUCUCUGUAUAAGGGUGACUGUGCCCAUGGAGGAUGGCAUGCAAUUGCCUAAAGAUUUCAGUCUGAGAAUCUGAGAAACGAUACUGAAUGGAGAUGACAGGCUUAGUGCCUGCUUCCAGGAGCCAUGCCUCCUCCUGGCCUGGAAUGAAUACCUAAACACCUGAGGCUCUGAGUUCCGGCAGUGUGCUGAAACUGCUGUUGGUCUGGCCCACUGACCCGGAAACCCAGCCACCUGAGGUUGUGACUUUAGGGCUUCUAGUUUUGUAUUUAGCUUUAAUUCCAUCUGUGAGGCAGUGGAGACUGUUCAUUUUAUUUUACAUCAAAGGCUUUUGGAGGUUGAGAUGGGAACAGGAUGAUAGAACAGUAAUGCAUAAUUAUGGAGCAUUUGCUGUAUGGCAGGCAUUCGUAAGAGUGCAUUUGUUGAUAUUAUUGUUUGGCCUCUCCUGUCAUUAGCCCUAAGCAGCUACACUUGCUAAGCUCUGUGCUAAGGCUGCAGUAAGCAGGCAGGCAGUGCGUGCUGGUGAGCUUGGGCAGUGCUGGAGUGUGUCUUGCCCAGUGUGGGGAUGAACAUACACCCUUUCAUGCUCACAGGUGCCUUAGCCUGGAUGAUAAUGUUUAAGUUCAUUCUGUUUAUAUGCACCGUGUCAUUAAACAAUGCUGUGAAAAGGGCACUAUUAUUUCCCCCAUAUUUUCAGUGAUAAGGCAGAGGCCCAUGGGCUCCUUGUAGCAAUGGAGGCAUUCCUUGAGGAUCCAGGCAAUCUGACUCCCGAGUCCCGGGGCUGGACAGAAGGAAGCUGGCUCCGAGAGCUAGACUGCAGUGCAGAGGAAUUCCACGCUCCGCAGGUGCUGUCUUCAGAAGUUGCAUCUCGUCAGCAGGAUGAGUGCUUUUGGAAUAGACAAUCUUAAAUGUCAUAGUGAGGUGACUUGCAGAGAUAAGGAAGGACGCCAGCCUCAGGCACUGACUGAUGAAUCCAGAUGGUGACUUCCUCCUUGCAGGAGAAUCAGCCACUUACACAGACUGGGAGGGAUUCUACUGAGGGAAAAAAUGAAUUCGCAGCCAGGGACAGUGGCUCAUGCCUGUAAUUCCAGCACUUUAGGAGGCUGAGGAGGCAGGAGGAUCACUUGAGCCCAGGAGUUCGAGACCAGCCUGGGCAACAGAGCAAGAUCCUGUCUCUACAAAAACAGAACAAACCAACAAUUAGCCAAGUGUGGUGGCACACACCUGUAGUCCCACCUACUCGGGAGGCUGAGACGGGAGCAUUGCUUAAGCCUAGGAGUUUGAGGCUGCAGUGAGCUAUGAUUGUGCCACUGUACUCCAACCUGGGUGACAGAGCAAGAAUGUUAAAAAAAAAAAAUUCUCAUUUCUUCUCAUGGACUUUGUGUGUGUGUGUGUGUGUGUGUGUGUGUGUGUGGUUGGUUGGUUGGUUUAAGCCAUGGAUUAAAGAAAGGAGAACUAUUUCCUGUGACUAAAAGUGGUUUACAUAUUGGUGCUUUAGCAGGAAUUUUGGAGGGUGGCUUAAGUGAAUAAUUAAAACAGAAAUCUUCCUAGACGAUGUUUAUCACACUCAAGACAUUAAAAAUUAGAGUCAAGGGACUGCUAAGACUUGGGGUGCUGGUGGGUGAGGCUGCCUUUCAGGGAGGCCAUGCUGUGAGUUGAGAAUCCUAGGCCACCUUGCCUGCACUGCCAGCUUUGCAGCUGUGGGCACAUCUGGAUCCCCAUUUCUGUGCGGGUGCAGACAGGUGAAUGUUACCUGCGUGCAUCAUAAAAUGCUGUGAAAGGGGUCACAGGUAUUGCCCAGGCUUGGGCAGACUCAUUCAUAGGGCUCACUGGCUUGCAUGAGAAGGGAUGCUGGGCACGGUAAACACAGAAGGAGAAGGCAGGCUCUGCUGCCAGGAGCUUGCACCCUGAGCCACGUGGAACUGGUUUGCCUGUGAAGCAAUAGGCACAGUCCUGAAAGAGCACAGUCCUGAAAGAGCACUUCUAAUUGGGCAUACAAGCAAGCUCAUAAUAAAGUUCUCCUAGGAAGUUUUCCUCAUGUUUUGAAGAUGAUACACUUAGUCCCUGACUGGGGAUGGUUUCGCUUACACUUUUUCAACUUUACGAUGGUGUGAAAGUGAUACACGUUCAGUACGUUCCUCAAUUAACAAUGAAGCUAUGUCCCGAUAAACCCAUCAUAAGUUGAAAAUAUCCUAAGUCCAUAAUGCACUUCUGAUAUAAUGGUAUUUUCAACUUACAGUGGCUUUACCAAGAUGUGGCGCAUUGUAAGUCGAGGAGCAUCCAUCCCUGAUGGGAUAUAUAAGGAUGAGAUUUAUGCACAGAUGUUCCUCAGCUUAUGAUGGGAUCAUGUCCCAGUAAAGACACUGUAAGUUGGAAACAUCUGAAGUCGAAAAUGCAUUUGAUAUACCUAAGCUAUCAAGCAUCAUAGCUUAGCCUCACCUGCCUUCAUUGUGCUCAGAGCACUUAAACGUUAGCCUGCAAUUGGGCAAGUCAUAUCCAAACAAUGCUGACAGCACCGCACACUGUAGGGUAUCAGUUGUUUAACUUCGUGACCGUGUGGCUGACUGAGAGCUGUGAAUCACUGACAUUGCCCGGCAUUGUCAGAGACUAUCCGACCGCAUAUCGCUAGCCCAGGAUAAGAGCAGAAUUCCAGAUUUGAAGUACAGUUUCUACUGAAGGCAUAUUGCUUUCGCACCAUCGUGAAGUCAGAAUUGUUAAGUCGAGCCAUGGUAAGUUGGAGACCAUCUGAAUAACAGGAUGAGAUGUAGAGCAGGAUAUAUAUGUUAGAAACAAAGUUUCGCGAACAGUGCAAACGUUUUCUAGAUGGACUAUCCUACUCUUCUCUAUCUCAUUAAACACUUUGCUGGCAGCAACUCACUGAGUUGAAUUCCCGCUCCACCAGUAGCCUCCCCUGGGCGUUGGAAGGCUCUGCCCUCUGAUGGGGGUCUCCCUGGGAGCUGCGGCUGCGGACCCCCGUAGAUGGGAUGCAGCUGCCCAGUGUGGUCCUUGCCUUUGCAGGUGAGCGGGUGCAGGGAGGUGCGGGGUGGGGUGGCGGCUGCAGCAGUGGUGGUUGGGGGCCCUGCAGGCUCCCUCGGGGUGUAGCAGGGACAUGGUGUGGUGGUUAACAGGAGUAGGCCACUCAUGUGGGACGUCAGGACUAGUGCCACAAAGGCAGCCCUGUCACACGAACAGGUUCUUGGGGGACAGAGGUCUGUCUGGGACUGGCUAAUGACCUGGAAAGACUGGAGAGGCACCAUUGUCCACCACCAGAUGUAUGGCUGCAGGGUAGGAGUAGACUUAAGAAGGAACACUGUUGGCUGGGCGCAGUGGCUCACGCAUGUAAUCCCAGCACUUCGGGAGGCCGAGGCAGGUGGAUCACCUGAGGUCAGAAGUUCAAGAACAGCCUGGUCAACAUGGUGAAACCCCAUCUCUACUAAAUAUACAAAAAUUAGCUGGGCGUGGUGGCAGGUGCCUGUAAUCCCAGCUACUCUGGAGGCUGAGGCAGAAGAAUCACUUGAACCUGGGAGGCGGAGGUCGCAGUGAGUUGAGAGAUCACGCCAUUGCCCUCCAGCCUGGGCAACAAGAGCGAAACUUCGUCUCCAAAAAAAAAAAAAAGAAGGAACACUGUUAGGGAGGCAGUCAGUGAGCCUCAAGUCAGAAAGACAAACAAGCUCAUUUUAUGCAUUUGCUAACAUUUGACCUCUUCUGGGACGCGUAGGUCUCUCAAGUUCUGUUUCUGUUUCCUGUCACGCAGAUCAGAGAUGUGAAACAGACCUGGUGUACACCCGUCUGGGGUAGCACUGGGAGCCACGGCGUCCUGGCAGAGCAGGUGUGCCUCCCACAGGCUGAUGCAGCCGUUCUCUGUGCAGAGGCUGAGCCAUCCUAGGAGCAGCUGUGGGGUGAAAGUGUCCUUCCUUAAACUUAGUGCUCCUGCUCAUUCUCUCAGUAUGGCUAAUAGCUCAUUUAAAUAUACUAUGGUGGUUUUUAAUUUUUGUGACUCAUUCCCUCCCCUCCUCACCUGUGUUUUUCCUGUGUGUCAGGGACAUUUUAGGGGGACCAAAAGGAUCUCUGUCUCUGCUCUGUGCUUGCUCUGAGGUUGAAUAGAGAAUGUUCAGGGCUGUUCUUAUUUGAGUCACUGGAGCUGUUGUGAGCUCUGACGGCCUGGGAGCCCCACUACUGUCACAUGAGGACAGGGCGUGGGGUGGCUCAAGCAUGGCCGCUUGGGGUUGGGUCCUAGUGCUGUCAUGUUGGAGGUGUCUGACCUUUGCACUAAGUUUCCCCACUUACACUAAAUGGGGAUAAUCAAAGCUUUGUGUGGGGAUUAAGUGAGUUAAUGUAACCAGAACACUUAGAAUGGUGUGCUGCAUACAGUGAUAAUGCAGAACUACUCACUGCUGCUGGAGUGCGCUGUUAUAUUCUUUAUUAGGUCCUCAGACUUUUUCUAUGCCUAAGCCUUGAGGGUCUCUCUCAGCUGUGCUUUUCUGUUUUUUUUUUUUUUGUCUUCAAUAGAUUUUUCUAGGGUCUUUUCUGGUAAAAAGAGACUGGGAAUGCAAAUACAUUGAGCAUGAGUUGAGAGGAGUUUGGACAUCAGCCUGACCGUGGAAAACUGGGGAGGCGUGGAGUAUAUAGUUUCCUCUGGGUGGGUUACUGACAGACCAUGGGAGUUCUGGGGAAAAUGUAUGCUCUUCUCUUUAAGUACAAGCCACCAUUGCCAGGCAGAAGCUGAUAAAGUAAUUAGAAUUGUUGUUCAUACCUGACUUGCAGGAAUGUGUGUGCGUGUGUCUGCAUGCGUGUGUACGUAUAUAUACUGUGCAUGCAUAUUUGUGUGUGUGUACAUACAUAUGUACACACUGCAUGUGUCUGCAUUUAUGUACAUAUGGGCAUGUGGCAUGGGCAUAUGGCACAUGCGUAUCUGUGCAUGCACACAUGUACACAGCACACAUGCACACAUGCAGUGCAUAGUAUGCCUGCAUGUACAUGUGCGUACCAUGCAUGCAUGUACCUACACGUGUGCAUACUAAUUUGUGCACACGUGCACACUGCAAUGUGUACUUACAUGCAAGCCUACGAUAUGUGUUUGCAGGCACAUACAUGUUCACACACUGCCCAUGCACAUUUGCAUACACAUGUGUGCAUGGAACAUAUGCAGUACAACACAAGUGUGUUUGCAUACAUGUACAAACACACAUGUGUAUUUACCUACAUUUCAAGGUGAACCCUCCCCAGAAGGCUCUGCUCAAUGAGACUCUGAAAGUGUUCAAAAGCAUGGUCUGAGAAAGCAUCCCUCCUUCAGGGCAUGUACCCAAGUAGUCUUUCUCUUGCUGGCUGAAAUCAUCAGGGAUUGUUUCCAAGUUUUAACUUCUGAUUUUCACUCUUUUAAAUCCCAGAGCCGAUACUUGAACAGAAGUAAGUUUGCUGUUACACCUCUCACUUUGAUUAGCUUGUUGCGUUAAAUUAAUUGUCAGAUUGCCUGAAACCAAAGCUUCUUAAAAUGAACACUGGUUCACUCGGGAAAUUUUUGCAAGAUCAAAAAUGGAAGACUGUGUCACUGAUGAAAGGGAGAGAUAGCCAGAAUACAAAAUCUAGAGCUUUGGACCUGAAAUCUGGCUGCAAGAUGGUUUUUUCCUGUCUUACCUAAGAAGUGGCCCCCAGGAUUCACAUACCAGUAGCCUCUUUUUGUUAUUCUUUUUUUUUUUUUUAAACAUAUCCCCUUGUUAAAGAUCCUCUUGAUUGCAAGCAAAAGCAGCCUACUGUGCAGGCUGGCUUAAGCAGAAAAGGGAAUUUAUUGUGGGGACAUGGUGGGGAGGUGUCUCAUUACUGAGAGGAAGAAGGCUGGCUGGCCUCAGAAGGCAUGAGAACUGGGACCUGGGUCCAGCCCAGUCCAUGGUGGCCACAGCUGGAUCUCAGCUCUGCUCCUCCAGGCCAGGUGGCUGCUUUCUCCUCUCUCUGCAGUGGGAUUUUCUCUGCCCAGGACUCAUGUGUCUACCUGUGGGUCUAAUCUCCUAGCAUAGGCUGAGCCUGCACCUCCUUGAGAAAACAGAUUAGCUUAGCUUAGUCUGAGUGUUCACUCCAGGCGCACCCUGAGAGGGAGUGCAGCCUGCACAUGGGGUGGGUAGUUCUUAAAGGGAGCCUGCCUCCAGAGGCGCCGGGGGAGGGGGGGGGCCUGCAUUUAGAGUGUGUGCGUGGAGCAUGUAGCUUGUUCCUGUUUUCAUGGAGUCGCAGAGAUCAGAAAGCAUUUAUGCCUGUUUCUGACAGAGAUGCACACAGCUGGUCUGAAUGGGCAGGAUUGGGGUGAGGGCAGUGGAGGAGGGAUCUGGCCACACAGGCAGUCUGCUGUGAGGGCCACUUCAAGCCACUCUUCCCUUGCUGAGCUGUGAUUCGUUCUUUUCCAAGUGACUUAAACAGAGGCCUUUUCUCUUGUUUGUGGGGAUGAGGAUGGCGAAGGGAGGAGGAGGGAGAGGGUGGCUGAGUGGAGGAAGCGCAGUUGUGCUGCGGAGAUUCCUGCUCUGCAGCUUGUCUGCUGUGGAUUGGCCCAGGGGGAAUCCAGUUUGCGCAGCACUUACAUGGCGGGCAAACUCCAGUUUAUACCUGGAGCUGCAGGGCGGAGCUGCUGUCAGCUGGGAGCUGUUAUUGAGGAACAGCUGUGGUAGAGGUGGAUAAGAAGAAGACCUGACCCCACCUGCUGGGGCAAGAAGCCUGCAUAGCACAGCUAAACAGCCAUGUGGGACAACGGCUGAGCAAUGACAGUGGAACCCAGUGUCCCAUGCAAAGUGCUCAAGAAGUGGACGGGAUGGAUCGCUGCUGAGUGGCUCUUGAGGAGCUCAGAGUAUCUUGGGGCUGAUGUUGCCUGUUGGGACUUUCCCCAGCACAGACAGCGUGCGGGAUUUCAGAUGCUCUUCUCCUUGCCUUCAGAAGCCCAGGGAGUGUUGGCAGCUUGUUUGCACCUGAUCAGAUAAAAGAGGUCAUGAUCUCUGUGAAGGUCUUUUCGGGGAAGGGGUCACUGGCCUUGCCAAAUGUGGGAAGCGAGGCCUCUUCCCAGUUCUGCCUGUGACUCAAUGGCUGUGGCUCAGGGCAAGUCAUUGGAUUUGUUUUUUGUUUUUUUUUUCAGAAUAACGUCAGCAUGUGCUGAGCAUCUGACUCACGGGGUGAGGCAGUGAAUGAAGGACUUCAUCUCCGUGAAGUGCUUGACGUGAUAGAAUGAAAACCCUUGCGUUCCCAGCCUUGGCUGUCAGAGUCUCAUUUUAAGGAAAGCCGUUUUUGACGUGUGUUUCCUUUCAGUUCGGAGCUGGCUUCUGUUAGGACAGGGGGUUUCUGCCCACUUAGCUGUGUCUCUGGUAAUCUGAGAUUCUUGGAAACGGGCCACAGUGAUUCCUCUGGCCACAUUCAGGGUCAGGUUUUCAGUUCGUCUUCCUGGUGUUUCCGCGCCUCAUUCUAGGGGGAGGUUUAGUCGUUCCUUUCUCUGCUGUCCCCCAGUAGCUUCCGGCCAUUCCUUGUGAAGGAAUCUUCCUAAGUCAAUUUUCCCUGGUGAAGACUGAGCCCUGGAAGAAGAGAACAAAUCUCAUCCUUUGUCACUUGGGAAUUUCACUGGCGAAAUUCAGUGAGGCACUUGAGGUUUGUAAAUGGGCAGACGUUUCCCACACGAUUACGUCUGUAUGUUGGAAAGAUAUUUCUAAGUUGUAGUGAGGUAGGAGGGAUUCUCAGCGAGAGGAGGGGCUUGGGCUGAACCCGGCACUGCUGGGACAUGAACAGGGGAAACAGCGUUGGCGGUGGAGCAGGUAGACAUUCCCUUGACCUCGUAAGUCCUGGAUGCCACCCGGCGAACUGGCCUGCGGGCUGGAAAUGAUGCAGCUGACCCAGUAAACGCACUCAGCUCACCUUUUAGUCUGGUCCAGAACGCUGAAUUGAGCUCUUGGAUCUUGGUGCUAAAUACGUGGUGUGGCAUUAAUGGCAGUAAAGAUGGAUGGUUAUGUACCAUGUAGAACGUGCAAAUCUGUUUUCAAUAGGCUUUAUUUUUUAGAGCAGUUUUGGGUUCACAGCAAAAUUGAGCAGAAGGUACAGAGAGUGCCUGUAUACCUGCUACCCCAACAUCCAGCUUCCCCUAUUAGUUUCCCUUCGCAAGAGUUAUAGUCCACAAACCUACACUGACACAUCCUUAAGUCUCCCAAGUCCACAGCUUACAUUAGGGUUCACUCUUUUUUUUUUUUUUUUUAAGAUGGAGUCUCACUCUGUCACCCAGGCUGGAGUGCAGUGGCAUGAUCUCGGCUCAUUGCAACCUCUGCCACCCGGGUUCAAGCGAUUCUCCUGCCUCAGCCUCCUAAGUAGGUGGGAUUACAAGCUCCUGCCACCACACCCAGCUAAUUUUUGUAUUUUUAGUAGAGACAGGGUUUUACUAUCUUGGCCAUGCCGGUCUUGAACUCCUGACCUUGUGAUCCACCUGCCUCGGCCUCCCAGAGUGCUGGGAUUACAGGAGGGUUCACUCUUGCUUUUGUACAUUCUAUGGGUUUGGACAAAUGUACAGACACACGUCUGAGAAAAUUGUGGGUUUGAUUUCAGGCCAUCACAUAAAGCAAAUACGGCAGUAAAGCAAGUCACACACAGUUUUUGGUUUCCUAGUGCAUACAAAGUUAUGUUUACACUGUAUUGCCGUCUGUGAAUAGGGCAGUAGCCUUAUGCCUAAACAAUGUACGGAUCUUAAUUUUAAAAUAUUUUAUUACUGAAAAAUGCUAAGGAUCAUCUGAGUUUUUAGCAAGUCGAGUCAUAGUCUUUUUGCCCAGAUGUUGAUGGCUGCUGACUGAUGACGGUGGUGGUGGUUGAAGGUUGAGGUGGUGGCUGCGACAGUUUCUUAAAAGAAGACAACAAUGAAAUUUGCCACAUUGAUGGACUCUUCCUUUCACAAAAGAUUUCUUUGUAGCAUGCGUUGCUGUUUAGCAUUUUGCCCACAGUAGGACUUCUUUCAGAAUAGGAGUCAGUUCCCUCAAACCCUGCCACGUCUUUGUCAAUUAAGUUUAUUCUGAAUCCUUUGUUGUAAUUUUGACAUGCUCACAGCAUGUUCCCUAGGAAUAGAUUCCAUCUCAGGAAACCACUUUCUUUGCUCUUCCAUGUCUUUUUCCAGGUUCUAUCAUGAGUUUGCAGCAAUUCAGUCACAUCUGUCGUCUCCACUUCUAGUUCUCUUGGUGUUUCCACCACAACUGCAGUUCCUUCUCCACUCUAGUCUUGAACCCCUCAAAGUCAUCCAUGAAGGUUGGAAUCAGCUUCUUCCACGCUCUGGAGGACUGGAAUGAAAUUGACCCCAUUAAAAAGAAAGACCUUCAUCACAGCAAUGGAGAAGAGAAAGCACAAAGCAUGGAGACCCUCCCUCCAGGGAAAGUACGGUGGCCAGACUUUAACCAGGAAGCUUAUGUUGGAGGGACGAUGGUCCGCUCCGGGCAGGACCCUUACGCCCGCAACAAGUUCAACCAGGUGGAGAGUGAUAAGCUUCGAAUGGACAGAGCCAUCCCUGACACCCGGCAUGACCAGUGUCAGCGGAAGCAGUGGCGGGUGGAUCUGCCGGCCACCAGCGUGGUGAUCACGUUUCACAAUGAAGCCAGGUCGGCCCUACUCAGGACCGUGGUCAGCGUGCUUAAGAAAAGCCCGCCCCAUCUCAUAAAAGAAAUCAUCUUGGUGGAUGACUACAGCAAUGAUCCUGAGGACGGGGCUCUCUUGGGGAAAAUUGAGAAAGUGCGAGUUCUUAGAAAUGAUCGACGAGAAGGCCUCAUGCGCUCACGGGUUCGGGGGGCCGAUGCUGCCCAAGCCAAGGUCCUGACCUUCCUGGACAGUCACUGCGAGUGUAAUGAGCACUGGCUGGAGCCCCUCCUGGAAAGGGUGGCGGAGGACAGGACUCGGGUUGUGUCACCCAUCAUCGAUGUCAUUAAUAUGGACAACUUUCAGUAUGUGGGGGCAUCUGCUGACUUGAAGGGCGGUUUUGAUUGGAACUUGGUAUUCAAGUGGGAUUACAUGACGCCUGAGCAGAGAAGGUCCCGGCAGGGGAACCCAGUCGCCCCUAUAAAAACCCCCAUGAUUGCUGGUGGGCUGUUUGUGAUGGAUAAGUUCUAUUUUGAAGAACUGGGGAAGUACGACAUGAUGAUGGAUGUGUGGGGAGGAGAGAACCUAGAGAUCUCGUUCCGCGUGUGGCAGUGUGGUGGCAGCCUGGAGAUCAUCCCGUGCAGCCGUGUGGGACACGUGUUCCGGAAGCAGCACCCCUACACGUUCCCGGGUGGCAGUGGCACUGUCUUUGCCCGAAACACCCGCCGGGCAGCAGAGGUCUGGAUGGAUGAAUACAAAAAUUUCUAUUAUGCAGCAGUGCCUUCUGCUAGAAACGUUCCUUAUGGAAAUAUUCAGAGCAGAUUGGAGCUUAGGAAGAAACUCAGCUGCAAGCCUUUCAAAUGGUACCUUGAAAAUGUCUAUCCAGAGUUAAGGGUUCCAGACCAUCAGGAUAUAGCUUUUGGGGCCUUGCAGCAGGGAACUAACUGCCUCGACACUUUGGGACACUUUGCUGAUGGUGUGGUUGGAGUUUAUGAAUGUCACAAUGCUGGGGGAAACCAGGAAUGGGCCUUGACGAAGGAGAAGUCGGUGAAGCACAUGGAUUUGUGCCUUACUGUGGUGGACCGGGCACCGGGCUCUCUUAUAAAGCUGCAGGGCUGCCGAGAAAAUGACAGCAGACAGAAAUGGGAACAGAUCGAGGGCAACUCCAAGCUGAGGCACGUGGGCAGCAACCUGUGCCUGGACAGUCGCACGGCCAAGAGCGGGGGCCUAAGCGUGGAGGUGUGUGGCCCGGCCCUUUCGCAGCAGUGGAAGUUCACGCUCAACCUGCAGCAGUAGGAGGGUCCGGGAGGCCCUGCCGUCCUGUCUCCUGCACCAUUGGGUGGAGUCUGGUGAUCACAUUAUUGAUUAUGUUUCUUAAACUUUCCGCGAAACUAAUAUACCUCAGUAUUCCAUCAUGGUCUGAAAGUCAAACUUCGGCAAGGCACGGACGACUGUGCAGACACAGCAGCGGCAAGAAGCGAGAACUGCCCUCCCCCUCCUCUCGGUGCAGCCCAGCCGGGCCCCCUUCCCCAGGCCGGAGCGCCCCUCUUCCUUCCAGCUUUCACUUCUGCCGGCUCCGCAACUGAGUGACACCCAGCGACAACCGACUGGGGAGUGGUAGAAGCAACUGAACGGAUGCGUGCGAGCUGAGGACAGGGCGGGAGGAGGGGGCACACAUGCCCCAGGGGAGCGAGGAGAACUCUUGAAAUCUCCAUUUUCAAUCCCUUCGAAAUCACGUAUGGUUUCCACAAAGCCGAGUCGUGUCACGUGGCAGGUUUACGUCAAUAGUCCCUCUCUCUGCUCCUCCAUUCGCAAGUGUCUUCCUGGGCCAGACUCCCCUCCACCUCAUGUACUUGCUAUAUUGAGGAUGAAGUUUUCUAUGGUGGGACACUAAAUAUAAAGCUAUAUAGAGAAAGAAUGUACGGUCAGUUCCCUAUGGUUUCUGUAGAUCAUCGUCAUCUUGUAUAUUCCCCACAAAGCCGUUCGCAGCUUCCGGGAGAAGGGGCCAGAGCCCGGUGGGGCCAGUUUCUCACAGAGGGAGGAGGUGGCCUUUGUCCCCUGGAGCCCGAUCAGCCAGUUGGUGCUACUGCUGUGGCCAGCUGGGGGGCUUCCUCCAGACCACCGGCCUCGGCCCCGGCAUCCCUGUUGGGCGUCAGCCUGAGAGUCCCUACUGUGCGUCAGAAUCCACCUUGCGUGCUGUGCGUAUCUGUGAACCUGGAGCGGUUACUUAUUUUGACAGAUAUCACUUUGGGUCUUUUUACAUUAAAUUUCUUUUCUCUAAGGAAUAUAAGACAUACCCCAUAGCUCUGUGUGAGCCAGCAAUACCGCUGCCCCCUGGCGACAGGGCAGACCAAUGAUGCCAGGCAGCUGUCACACGCUAGUAUUGGCUUCAUUGUGAUCUGAGCCCUGCACGCUGGGCCUUCAGAAUUAAUGGCCAGCAGUGUCAGGGAUGAGCCCGUCAGCCAGGGCACAGGCCUGGCUCACAGUCCUGCACACCUGCUGGCCUGGGGAGCUCCAGCCAGGCAGCGAGUCCUGCCCCGCCCGCAGCUCCCUCCCACACCCCGCCUGGCCAAGAUGACUGCUUCAGGGGGCUUUGGGGAAAGAAUUAGGAAGGGUCAGAACCAAACAAUACCUGCUCAUUUACACUGAGGAUUCAGGGCGGGAGACAGGAGCCUUGGGGUCCUGUUAAACCACAGACAGUUAUGAACUGAAAGUCAUAACGGGGAGAGGUGCCUGGCUUCUACCUGGGUGCUCAGGAAUGUUCCUCGUCACCCCUGCCACUCUGUGGUCGGUGCCCUGCUUCCUCCUCCACUCCUGGCCGCCUUCUCCAGCGCCGCACACACAGAUGCUCAGUCUCAGAGAGGCUGGCACGGCCUGGCAGUCUGAGAAAAGCGUCAGUUAGGCACACCUGCAGGCCCCUCGGUGGGACAGCGGCGGCCUUGGAGUUAGGAGCCACCCUGGGAGGUUGUGCCGGUGCCAUGCUCCUCCCUGUGUCUUGUAUGAAAGGGGCCACUGUGUGUCUUCCUCCCCGGCGGGAGCCCCACAUGUGUGCACUGUAGGACAGCGGCCCCGAGGUGGAAGCCUGGCUGGAGGGCUGCCCUAUAGGUCUUCUCUUCCCGCCUCCCCUGCCAUGCAACCAGAUGUGUUGUGAGUGGGCAGCGUGCCCCCACGCUGGAGUAACUCCGCACGCUUCUGUCUUUCACGGUGGGCGCUCGGGGGGAGCCUGAGGAAAACCCCCUUAGGUACCUGUGCGAGGCUGUGGAGUGCAGGCCAGAGCAGGGUGUGCGUAGCCCCCAGCACCCAGGUUCUUCUGUCAGACCCUGUGACCUGCGAGCUGCUACUACUGUAAGGAGGGAAAUGGAUGAAUCUGGCUCGUUUUAAAAUCACGUUUUCUGACGAAUCCUUUGCCCCUUCACCUUUACCCCGCCCGCACCCCUAGGCCCUCUCAGCCUUCCUAUCAUCCCACGUGUCUACCCAGACCCUUGUGCGGCCCAUGCCCUGGGGGCGGCGUCCUGUCCCUGAGCUGGGAGGCGGCUUUGGAUGGUCCGGGCGUCAAGAGCAGGGGUGGGCCGGGGAGGGGUCCUUUGCGGUGAGCUAUGUUUACAUGACACAGUGUGCCAAAGUGACUUACUGCGGUUGCGUUAGUUUUUAAUCAUCAGGACUAUCUCACCCUCCCACUCCUGUUUUUAAAACUCAGAAUUCUUUCCUAAGAGCCCUUCGAGCAAAGCGUGCCGAAGUUAGUUGUCUUCUCUGUGCUGGUCCUUUCUUAUGUCCUCAUAAAAGCUCAGAUGAUGGUAUCUGUGAGUAUGUUUUGCAAAUUCAAAAUAUAGUUUGGUAAUUUUUUUUUCCAGUUGAUUUUUAAAAAGAACUGCUGUACAGAGCUUGUACUUUGUCCAUUUUAUAGAUGGAAACCAUCCUUGAAAAUUGUUUAACUUAAAUAAAGAGAAGAUACUUUCUAGA